GAGUCGGGAAAAUGGCUGCGAGUACCUCCAUGGUCCCGGUGGCUGUGACGGCGGCAGUGGCGCCUGUCCUGUCCAUAAACAGCGAUUUCUCAGAUUUGCGGGAAAUUAAAAAGCAACUGCUGCUUAUUGCGGGCCUUACCCGGGAGCGGGGCCUACUACACAGUAGCAAAUGGUCGGCGGAGUUGGCUUUCUCUCUCCCUGCAUUGCCUCUGGCCGAGCUGCAACCGCCUCCGCCUAUUACAGAGGAAGAUGCCCAGGAUAUGGAUGCCUAUACCCUGGCCAAGGCCUACUUUGACGUUAAAGAGUAUGAUCGGGCAGCACAUUUCCUGCAUGGCUGCAAUAGCAAGAAAGCCUAUUUUCUGUAUAUGUAUUCCAGAUAUCUGUCUGGAGAAAAAAAGAAGGACGAUGAAACAGUUGAUAGCUUAGGCCCCCUGGAAAAAGGACAAGUGAAAAAUGAGGCGCUUAGAGAAUUGAGAGUGGAGCUCAGCAAAAAACACCAAGCUCGAGAACUUGAUGGAUUUGGACUUUAUCUGUAUGGUGUGGUGCUUCGAAAACUGGACUUGGUUAAAGAGGCCAUUGAUGUGUUUGUGGAAGCUACUCAUGUUUUGCCCUUGCAUUGGGGAGCCUGGUUAGAACUCUGUAACCUGAUCACAGACAAAGAGAUGCUGAAGUUCCUGUCUUUGCCAGACACCUGGAUGAAAGAGUUUUUUCUGGCUCAUAUAUACACAGAGUUGCAGUUGAUAGAGGAGGCCCUGCAAAAGUAUCAGAAUCUCAUUGAUGUGGGCUUCUCUAAGAGCUCGUAUAUUGUUUCCCAAAUUGCAGUUGCCUAUCACAAUAUCAGAGAUAUUGACAAAGCCCUCUCCAUUUUUAAUGAGCUAAGGAAACAAGACCCUUACAGGAUUGAAAAUAUGGACACAUUCUCCAACCUUCUUUAUGUCAGGAGCAUGAAAUCGGAGUUGAGUUAUCUGGCUCAUAACCUCUGUGAGAUUGAUAAAUAUCGUGUAGAAACGUGCUGUGUAAUUGGCAAUUAUUACAGUUUACGUUCUCAGCAUGAGAAAGCAGCCUUAUAUUUCCAGAGAGCCCUGAAAUUAAAUCCUCGGUAUCUUGGUGCCUGGACACUAAUGGGACAUGAGUACAUGGAGAUGAAGAACACGUCUGCUGCUAUCCAGGCUUAUAGACAUGCCAUUGAGGUCAACAAACGGGACUACAGAGCUUGGUAUGGCCUCGGGCAGACCUAUGAAAUCCUUAAGAUGCCAUUUUACUGCCUUUAUUAUUAUAGACGGGCCCACCAGCUUCGACCCAAUGAUUCUCGCAUGCUGGUUGCUUUAGGAGAAUGUUACGAGAAACUCAAUCAACUAGUGGAAGCCAAAAAGUGUUAUUGGAGAGCUUACGCCGUGGGAGAUGUGGAGAAAAUGGCUCUGGUGAAACUGGCAAAGCUUCAUGAACAGUUGACUGAGUCAGAACAGGCUGCCCAGUGUUACAUCAAAUAUAUCCAAGAUAUCUAUUCCUGUGGGGAAAUAGUAGAACACUUGGAGGAAAGCACUGCCUUUCGCUAUCUGGCCCAGUACUAUUUUAAGUGCAAACUGUGGGAUGAAGCUUCAACUUGUGCACAAAAGUGUUGUGCAUUUAAUGAUACCCGGGAAGAAGGUAAGGCCUUACUCCGGCAAAUCCUACAGCUUCGGAACCAAGGCGAGACUCCUACCACCGAGGUGCCUGCUCCCUUUUUCCUACCUGCUUCACUCUCUGCUAACAAUACCCCCACACGCAGAGUUUCUCCACUCAACUUGUCUUCUGUCACGCCAUAGUUGGCUACUCUCAAGCCAGCACAUUGUUAGACCCAUCUUAAUUAAGCCUUACCUCCAUGUAAAGAACAGCACGUCUGUUCCAAGGACCUCAGCUCUUCUUGUUUCUACAGAUGGCAACAGCUCCAUAGGGACAGCUUGUAUAAUUACCUUCAGAGGCCAACUGACAGAAUCCUGGCAGGAACAGACAUUAUCUUGCCAGUUAGAAGUACUUCUGUCUCACUUAUGUCCAAAGAGUGGCUAUAGAUCUUGGCCUUCUUCCCUGAAUGCUUUUUUUUUUUGGCCCCCAAGAAAGUCCCUUUUAUAGCACUUUAGCACAGGCAAUGCUACAGGAACAAAGUUUCAAUGCUGCUGAGAGUGAAAGAAAGGAGGAAAGUCUGCCACUCUACCCUGAGCUGGCAGUAGGGCACUGAGUACCCUAGGAAGAAGUCAGAGCAAUGGAUACAAAUGACCUUGCUCUUGGAUUUGCUGAGCAUGAUCCCUAUUCUGAUGUCAGAGAUUAGGUUUAAAUGGAAUAGAGCUAUCCAUUUGUUCUUACUCUCUAGGGAGACAAUCUUCCAAAACAGUUUUGGGGGGGUCUUCUAAAGCUUUCAAAUUGGAAGUAACUUUAUUCAACUAGAGUUGAAUAAAAGAAGGGCAAAAAUAAUCUCACAGAGCUUGGAACUGCUGAUAGCCCUUACUGAGGGCAAAAGAUGGCUAUAUUGUUAGCUAUACUCCUACCAAAGCAAGCAAGGAGAUAGGAUUAUAGAUAAUUUCACGGACAUUUGGAAAUAACAUUGGUGAUUAUACAGACAAGAAUAAACUCACUUCAAGCUGGUCUGUUUUAAUAAAUUUUCAACGUAAUUGUCUAUUUUUUUCCCUCCCAUCUGCAACAGAAUACAUUUUUUUCAGCCUUUAUCUAGAUGAGGUAAAGGGAAUCAUUCUUAUGGUGCUCUUGGAGAGUUUCAGGCCUGUGCAUGUGUGUACAGCAGGAGGUAAUAUGCUAUAAUGUCUGCUGUAAUAUAUUUGCACAGUAGAUGCUAUGGAUCAUUCUGAGCUCAGGGUCCAGACUUUAUUCUUAUUCCCAGAAUUUUGUGUUACGUUUUUACCUCCUAACAUAUGACACUUCAUCUUAUAUUAAGGAAGGUUUAGAAUAUCUAAUACGACUUGAAUUCAUUUGUUACUAAGCCUUCUCAGGCAAGCUGUAUACUAGUUACUGGUCUCCACUGCCAUGCCUUUUCAAGGUUCCCAUGGUCCAGAAUGAUGUUUGAUUCUUAAUUUUUCUGUCCCUUUUAUAAUUUGUUUUAAUGAUUUUGCUACAUUUGGAAUUCAAUAAAAAAUGUGAACAAUAA